ACUCGUGCGUGAGGCGAGAGGAGCCGGAGACGAGACCAGAGGCCGAACUCGGGUUCUGACAAGAUGGCCGGGCUGCCCCGCAGGAUCAUCAAGGAAACCCAGCGUUUGCUGGCAGAACCAGUUCCUGGCAUCAAAGCCGAACCAGAUGAGAGCAACGCCCGUUAUUUUCAUGUGGUCAUUGCUGGCCCUCAGGAUUCCCCCUUUGAGGGAGGGACUUUUAAACUUGAACUAUUCCUUCCAGAAGAAUACCCAAUGGCAGCCCCUAAAGUACGUUUCAUGACCAAAAUUUAUCAUCCUAAUGUAGACAAGUUGGGAAGAAUAUGUUUAGAUAUUUUGAAAGAUAAGUGGUCCCCAGCACUGCAGAUCCGCACAGUUCUGCUAUCGAUCCAGGCCUUGUUAAGUGCUCCCAAUCCAGAUGAUCCAUUAGCAAAUGAUGUAGCGGAGCAGUGGAAGACCAACGAAGCCCAAGCCAUAGAAACAGCUAGAGCAUGGACUAGGCUAUAUGCCAUGAAUAAUAUUUAAAUUGAUACGAUCAUCAAGUGUGCAUCACUUCUCCUGUUCUGCCAAGACUUCCUCCUCUUUGUUUGCAUUUAAUGGACACAGUCUUAGAAACAUUACAGAAUAAAAAAGCCCAGACAUCUUCAGUCCUUUGGUGAUUAAAUGCACAUUAGCAAAUCUAUGUCUUGUCCUGAUUCACUGUCAUAAAGCAUGAGCAGAGGCUAGAAGUAUCAUCUGGAUUGUUGUGAAACGUUUAAAAGCAGUGGCCCCUCCCUGCUUUUAUUCAUUUCCCCCAUCCUGGUUUAAGUAUAAAGCACUGUGAAUGAAGGUAGUUGUCAGGUUAGCUGCAGGGGUGUGGGUGUUUUUAUUUUAUUUUAUUUUAUUUUAUUUUUGAGGGGGGAGGUAGUUUAAUUUUAUGGGCUCCUUUCCCCCUUUUUUGGUGAUCUAAUUGCAUUGGUUAAAAGCAGCUAACCAGGUCUUUAGAAUAUGCUCUAGCCAAGUCUAACUUUAUUUAGACGCUGUAGAUGGACAAGCUUGAUUGUUGGAACCAAAAUGGGAACAUUAAACAAACAUCACAGCCCUCACUAAUAACAUUGCUGUCAAGUGUAGAUUCCCCCCUUCAAAAAAAGCUUGUGACCAUUUUGUAUGGCUUGUCUGGAAACUUCUGUAAAUCUUAUGUUUUAGUAAAAUAUUUUUUGUUAUUCUACUUUGCCUUUGUACAGUUUAUUUUACUGUGUUUAUUUCAUUUUCCCAAUUUGACAAUCGUAUUUUAAAAUUGAAACUGAUGGAACAUUCUUUCUUGGUCUUCACCAUCUGACAAAUUGAAUGGCAAGAGGUGGAUUUUGCCAGUUUCUUUUCACUGAUGCAGAUUUGUGUUAAGAUAGUACUGAAUGGAGUAUUUAUAAACUGGCCCUGAGCAUGCAUAAAGCAUCAGUAUCUGACCUUUUUUUAACCUUCUAGGAAUUUGAAAUAAAUGUGUUUGUGUUGUCUGAUUAGAUGAUCAUUGGUGUCUUGCCACAAUGUUUAAAAAUUACUGUACAGGAAAGUCACAGCAAAGAUAGCAGUUGUGACUGACAUGUAGGACUUUCACAGUUGUGCCACAUUUUUGCCUAAAAUUUGGGUUAUGACAUUUUUCUUGGUUCUUAUCUGAAAAUUUCAUCUGUAACCUUUCAUGUGUGUUAAGAAACACUGAUCUGAUCAUUUGGGAUUUGCUGAGGCAUUUGUGAGUCUUCCUUAUAAACCUGAUGAGCAGAUCUCAACUAUCUAGCUUGUGUGUCAUCAGAAAGGUUUAUCCCUUUGAGAGUAUCAAGUCCUCAGUUAAUGAUUCUUGCUUUCAUCCCUCCAGUAUUUGCUGUGGGAGCUCGUUUUAUUCUUUAAUUUGGAAUUCAGUAAUUUUUCUUCUUUAUUGACGAAUUCCUCCCCUCACAAAACUGUUCUUUCCCACCUCUCUCCAUAUCUAAUUCCUGAUUCUUGUUAUUUUUAAGUCAUAAAUGUAGCCAGUCAUAAAUACAUAAAUGUUAACCUUCGGGUUGCAACCUUGUCUCUUGCAGUUUAAGGUAAUGGAUAUUGUAGCCCAUUUGAAUUUUCUUCACUCUUAUUCUCGUAAUUCUGGAGUUUCUUCAGAUUGUGGUGUAUUUUAUUGUGCUCCUAUGUAAGAUGAAGAAUUAACUAUUAAAAUUACAUUUUCAACAUACAAAAGCUUUUGAUGACUGGUAACUGGUAUCCUUCCAAAUAAAUGCAUUGCUUGGUAACAAAUGUUAGCUUAAUUCAGAAUGAAAUAGUUAACAACCCUAAUAUUGUAAAAUUUGAAAACUGAUAGCAGCUGUCAUUUAUAACAAUUCUUGGGCUGUUUAAAGGGUACAUUUGACUAUAGCUAAGGAAAUUGAAUCUCACUUUAAAAAUGAACCACACAAAACUUCAAGAAACGAAAUAGAAAUCAACAUUUACUGCCCGUAAUAUUGCUCAUGGUUAUAGCUAGUAUCACAUAGUGAUUUACAAACCAUGAAAUUCCAGAUUUAAAUCUGUUGCACUACAAAAAUGUCUAAAUGAUGUCUGCUAAAUUUGUGAGUUAUAGAAGUACAGAAAUAAGUCAUUUUCAUUUCAAAUGCAGUGAAUUUCUAAUUUCAUGGUAUCAUAUUUUUUUCCUUUGCAGUUUUGGUAAGACUCCCCCAUUACUUUGCUAAGACUUGCUUUCUCAACCAGUGGGAUGAAACGAGUGCCAGUGUGUUGACUGAGCCUUCUUAGGACUUAAGGGGCUCUGGGAGAGGCCAAGGCAGCAGUUGAAAACUGCAGCUUCACCUGGCCUUUGGGCCUGUUUUCCCUGGCCCACACAGUGUGGCUGGUUAAAACAUUCUGAAUUUGAUGCCAACAUUUUUAAAAAUUGGGAGAUUUGCAUGAAAAUCCAGAAUUCGGGUAACUUUUGAAUGAUCUGAAGAUCUGGCAACAGUAGACCUGACCCACCUUUGUGCACGGGACUUAACUGAGAGGAUCUGAGUAGCAGACACCCUAAGAGCAUGUCAUUGUCUUCUCACCAGUUACUCUCCAGUUGGCUAGAGUCCCCUCCGAGCACACCUGCUAGUCCUUCCCCCUUGUAAGCCUUUGACUUUGUAAUCCCUGGGCUAAAGGAAACACAUUAUUCAACAAAAGUGUUUCAUGUUUGCCCACUAGUUGUUGGGGAUGAUUAGGUGGUGAGUGAAUGGCAUGGGGCUUUCCUUUGGGGACCAUAUACUCUAAUGGGGAAGGGGGACAGACAAAUAGUUGUAACUCUGUCAUGGAAAAGAGAAGUAACUUGGACAGACUUUUGGAUUCAGGCCAGAUGAACAUCUCCAGGCAGAGGGAACAGCAGCAUCUGCAAAGUCCUGGGAGAGAAGAAAAGAAUCUGAACAUUAAGUGGCUUCCUGAAAAUCGACUGCCCAGGCCGGGCACAGUGGCUCAUGCCUGUAAUCCCAGCACUUUAGGAGGCCAAGGCAGGAGGAUCACUUGAGUCCAGGAGUUUGUGACCAGCCUGGCUAACAUAGUGGGACCCAGUCUUUAUUUAAAAGAAAAUUGCCCGUUAAGAGGCUUUUCUAAAAUCUUGAGGUGUUGAUAGGAGCUUUAUGUUUUUUGACUUGAUUGUUGUAGUCUACUUCGCUGCGAUUUGCUUCUGCUCUAGUUAUCCUUCAUCCUCUCAAAGGCUGUCUAGCAAGAUCUUAGGUCUAAAGUAAAGUCAUCUCUUGGUAUUUGUCGGGAACUGGUUCUAGGACUUCCUUUGGAUAUCCAAAUUCGCAGAUGCUCAAGUCUCUGGAAUAAAAUGAUGUUGUAUAUGCAUACAAUCUACACAAAUCCUCCCGCUUAUGUUAAUAUUUAGAUUACUUAUAAUACCUAUUAUAAUGUAAGUGCUAUGUAAAUAGUUACACUAUUGUUUAAGGAAUAAUGACAAAAAUAUACAUGUUGACUACAGACACAAUGUUUUUUGGAAUAUUUUGUCUGGUUGUUUGAAUCCACGGAAGUGGAACCCAUGGAUAUGGAGGGCCAACUAUAUAGAACCUUACUCUAGACCAAGAAUGUACUUGUAAAACAAUUUCAAAGAAGCACUUAAAAAUAAGAUUAAAUACAAACCAACAGAUAAAAGUCACAGGUGCUAUGGUUGUUUGAUGGAGAAUGGGGAAGGAAAUCUGUCCUAAAAGACAUUAUAAACACAGUGACCUAAGUGGAACUAAAUUGGAUCGAGGAAAUGAUAGGAAUAGGCCUCAUUUUUCUGUUGAAUGGUUCAGGAACCUUUUUUUUUUUUUUUUUUUUUUUUUUUUUUGGCUGCUCUAGCCACUUUCUAGCUCUGUAGUUUAGGCUGGAGUGCUGUGGCAUGAUCUUGGCUCACUGCAGGUUCUGCCUCCCGCGUUCAAGCGAUUCUCCUGCCUCAGCCUCCUGAGGAGCUGGGACUACAGACACCUGCCACCACACCUGGCUAAUUUUUUGUAUUUUUAGUAGAGACGGGGUUUCACCAUGUUGGGCCAGGAUGGUCUCCAUCUCCUGACCUCGUGAUCUGCCCGCCUCGGCCUCCCAAAGUGCUGGGAUUACAGGCGUGAGCCACCGUGCCCAGCCCUGCCACAUCUUUUUUGUUAGUUGCAGUAGCAAUACAACCUUAUCUAGAAAAGCUGGCCAAAAAAGAAAAUACCAUGAUAAUAGGGUACCUAAUUUAUUGCUUUAUUUAAGAAAAAUGUAAUAUUUCAUUCGAAUAAGUACUUUUGGGCUGGGAUGAUAUUUCAUUUAGCUACUUGGCAUGCCACCCAUCUUAGGGAAUUAUAUGAGGGUUUAUACUUUAAAUAACAUAAAAAGCAAAACAUGCUGAAUGUAAUAAUUUGAGAGAAGUGUAAAUAAUAAAAAUCUGUCAUCUACCACCUGGA